CUCAGCGAAGAUGGCGGCAGUGGAGAAGCGGCGGCAAGCGGUACCACCGCCGGCCGGUUUCACGGACAGCGGCCGCCAGUCGGUAUCCCGGGCGGCGGGGGCGGCCGAGAGCGAGGAGGACUUCCUGCGGCAGGUCGGCGUGACGGAAAUGCUACGUGCGGCCCUGCUGAAGGUGCUGGAGGCGCGGCCCGAGGAGCCGAUCGCCUUCCUGGCUCACUACUUCGAGAACAUGGGCCUGCGCUCGCCUGUAAACGGCGGCGCCGGGGAGCCCCCGGGCCAGCUCCUGCUGCAGCAGCAGCGCCUGGGCCGCGCGCUAUGGCACCUUCGCCUGGCCCACCACUCCCAGAGGGCCGCCUUCAACAACAACGUGAGCGUGGCCUACGAGUGCCUGAGCGCCGGCGGGCGCAGGAAGAGGCCGGGGCUGGACGGGCGCACCUACAGCGAGCUGCUCAGGCGCAUCUGCCGGGACGGCCAAGCCCCCGAGGAGGUGGUGGCGCCGCUGCUGCGCAAGGUGCAGUGCCGUGACCACGAGGCGGUGCCGCUGAGCGUCUUCCGCGCGGGCACACUCACCUGCUUCGUGCUGCUGGAGUUCGUGGCGCGCGCCGGCGCGCUCUUCCAGCUGCUGGAGGACUCGGCCGCCGCCGUGGCCGACCGCCGCGUGGGCCAGGCCGUGCUGGACACCCUGGAGGGCGCGCUGCAGGCCAGCGACGCCGCCGCGCCCGCGCGCUUCCUGGAGGCCGGCUCGCGCUUGGGGCCCGACAGCCUGGCGCUGGCGCUGGACCGCGCCGUCGGGGGGCGGCGGCCCAGCGCGCCCAUGACCCGCGAGGAGUUUCUGGAGAGGGCCGCCGCGCUCUUCAUCGCGAAGGUCAAGCCGGUGGGCUGAGGCCCGUGGGCCGCGCGGAUCCGGGAUCUGCGCUGGGGGGUCCCCGCGUGCGGGGCGCGCGGAGCCUUCCCUUCGCCCUGGUGAGGCCCUGCCAUAACCAGGCGCCCAGCCCUGCGGAGGAGGCCGGGGCUCCCAGGAAGCGGACGCCCGGUCCCCACACAGCGCCGCGGCCGCCCCUCCACCCCCGCGGGAGCCCCUGCCCCACGCUAAUAAAAUGUGUUGCGAGGCUGA